UCCGGCUGAGAGUCCUUCUAGCGGCGCCGGUGAGUCCGCGUGUGGAAGUCUGUGAGGCGCAGAGGUGGGGCAGGCCGUCUGACUAGCUAGGCGGCUGGGAGCGUUUUCGUGGCGGGGAACGGAGGUUGAAUUGCCCUGCCUGGGCUCAUAGGGAAGGAGGAUGUGAAGGAGCUUGUGAAGGCAGAGGAAGGUAACUUUCGUCUGGGGAGCCGCAGAGUAGGGAGGGAAGCUGCAGGCCGUCUCUCCCUAAGUAAAAGCGCGACUUUUAGAAAUGAUGGUUCAGGGUUCGAGUUUGUGACCCGCUUGAGAAAGUGACCAACCUCUGAGCCUGAAUCCCAUACCUGAAAAACAAGGACAGUAAUCACCCUUGCCAGUUUCACAUAGCUUGAUUAUUGAAUAAUAAAAUACAGUUUUGAAAAAAAUGGAUGAAGAACCUGAAAGAACUAAGCGAUGGGAAGGAGGCUAUGAAAGAACAUGGGAGAUUCUUAAAGAAGAUGAAUCUGGAUCACUUAAAGCUACAAUAGAAGACAUUCUAUUCAAGGCAAAGAGAAAAAGAGUAUUUGAGCACCAUGGACAAGUUCGACUUGGAAUGAUGCGCCACCUUUAUGUGGUAGUAGAUGGAUCAAGAACAAUGGAAGACCAAGAUUUAAAGCCUAAUAGACUGACGUGUACUUUAAAGUUGUUGGAAUACUUUGUAGAGGAAUAUUUUGAUCAAAAUCCUAUUAGUCAGAUUGGAAUAAUUGUAACUAAGAGUAAAAGAGCUGAAAAAUUGACUGAACUUUCAGGAAACCCAAGAAAACAUAUAACGUCUUUGAAGGAAGCUGUGGAUAUGACCUGCCAUGGAGAGCCAUCUCUUUAUAAUUCCCUAAGCAUGGCUAUGCAGACUCUAAAACACAUGCCUGGACAUACAAGUCGAGAAGUACUAAUCAUCUUUAGCAGCCUUACAACUUGCGAUCCAUCUAAUAUUUAUGAUCUAAUCAAGACCCUAAAGGCAGCUAAAAUUAGAGUAUCUGUUAUUGGAUUGUCUGCAGAAGUUCGCGUUUGCACUGUACUUGCUCGUGAAACUGGUGGCACGUACCAUGUUAUUUUAGAUGAAAGCCAUUACAAAGAGUUGCUCACACAUCAUCUUAGUCCUCCUCCUGCUAGCUCAAGUUCUGAAUGCUCACUUAUUCGUAUGGGAUUUCCUCAGCACACCAUUGCUUCUUUAUCUGACCAGGAUGCAAAACCCUCUUUCAGCAUGGCGCAUUUGGAUGGCAAUACUGAGCCAGGGCUUACAUUAGGAGGCUAUUUCUGCCCACAGUGUCGGGCAAAGUACUGUGAGCUACCUGUUGAAUGUAAAAUCUGUGGUCUUACUUUGGUGUCUGCUCCCCACUUGGCACGGUCUUACCAUCAUUUGUUUCCUUUGGAUGCUUUUCAAGAAAUUCCCCUAGAAGAAUAUAAUGGAGAAAGAUUUUGUUAUGGAUGUCAGGGGGAAUUGAAAGACCAACAUGUUUAUGUUUGUGCUGUGUGCCAAAAUGUUUUCUGUGUGGACUGUGAUGUUUUUGUUCAUGAUUCUCUACACUGUUGCCCUGGCUGUAUUCAUAAGAUUCCAGCUCCUUCAGGUGUUUGAUUCCAGCAUGUAGUAUACAUUGUAUGUGUUAAAAAGAAAUUUGCAACUGUGAAUAAAAGGACUUCUUUAGAAGAAGCUUCAUUUAAAACAUGAAAGGAUAAUCUGACUUAAGAAACUUUUUGCUAAGAAAAGGUAAUAUUUUAUUAAAUUUUAAAUUUGUGUUGUCACAGAAAUACCUGAAAUUCAGUAGUACUUCAUUCAAUUAAUUUUGUUUUCUAUUAUUUUGAGUUAUACUGUUUUCAAAGUCAUUAUGCAGUAUGUAUAAACUUAUAAGAAUUAAAUUGAUGUGAUAAUUUUAUGUUUUUAUAAUUAAAUAUAGAAUCUUUAUGAUUUAUGUUAAUUCAUUAAUUUAGUGUAAGAAGAAAGUUAAGUCUGAAUGUAAAUUCAGUGUAAGAUGAAAAUUUAUCAAUACUUAUGAAAUUAGGCUGGGCGCUGUGGCUCACACCUGUAAUCCCAACACUUUGGGAGGCUGAGGUGGGCAGAUCACUUGAGGUCAGGAGUUCGAGACCAGCCUGGCCAACAUGGUGAAACCCCGUCACUACUAAAAAUACAAAAAAUAAUUAGCCGGGCAUGGUGGUUCACGCCUGGAGUCCCAGCUACUUGGGAGGCUGAGGCAGGAGAAUCGCUUGAACCCAGGAGGCGGAGGUUGCAGUGAGCCGAGAUUGUGCCACUGCACUCCACCCUAGAGUAAGACUCCCUCUCAAAAAAAAAAAAAGUUAUGAAAUUAAUACAUAUGAAAUGAUGUACUGCUACAUCCACCAGAGAGGUCUUUUUAGGUUUAACCAAACAUCUGGAAUAUGUUUAUCAAGUUAGUACAUCUGAAAUUAUUUGUGGCUAUGACCAACAGAAGUCACUUUACAUUAAACAUUCAAACUCACAAGACUGCCAUGGCCAUACUUGGUACCCGCUUACUCAGAAGGAUAUUAAACAGAAACAACAGCCUGCCAGCACAGCAUCAAGCAGUCCUCAUUAGCAGUGGAAGUCCUUGUAGCAGUCCACUAGUACAAUUUGGGUGCAAGGAGAUAAGAUCCUCCACAGGCAUCAAGGAACCAAUAUCUCUUAACAAUUCCAUAAACACAGCUUCCAGGUAUCCACAAGGGAUGUGUCAAUUUCAAGAGUCACUACACUCAGGAAAGCCUAAAGCUUGAAGACUCCAUUUAUUUAUAGUGCAUCCCAAUCCAGAUACGUAACAAUUAACGAGUUAUUUUUACUAUAAGCAAAGUUGCCUAAAAUCAUAGUUGAUACUAACCAUGGUUAACAGAGCUCUAAAGUUUGACAGAAAGUGAGAUUCAAAUCCUUUCACUCUCAUAUGCUAAACCUUUUGCCUUACUCUGGGUCAUCAGAGAAAUUUAGGUGAGAAUGUAUGAUGAAGUCUGUGUUUUAGAUUCAAUGCAGAUAUAUCAUUGUGGGCAGAACUCUUUCUGGUUAUAUCCAGUUAAGAGUAAAUCAGGCUUUCAGCCGGGCGCGGUGGCUCACGCCUGUAAUCCUAGCACUUUGGGAGGCCGAGGCGGGCAGAUCACGAGGUCAGGAGAUCGAGACCAUCCUGGCUAACACGGUGAAACCCCGUCUCUACUAAACAUACAAAAAAUUAGCUGGGCCUGGUGGCGGGCGCCUGUAGUCCCAGCUAUUCGGAAGGCUGGGGCAGGAGAAUGGUGUGAACCCAGGAGGCGGAGCUUGCAGUGAACCGAGAUCGCUCCACUGCACUCCAGCCUGGGCGACAGAGCUAGACUCUGUCUCAAGAAAAAAAAAAAAAAAAAAAAAAAAAAGAGUAAAUCAGGCUUUCAUAGCAAAGGUAUGUCUAUUUUAUGUAUAUAAACUUCAGGUACUCUAACUUGAGUUUCACUAUGAAAUUUGUGAUUUUUUUUUUUUUUUUUUUGAGAUGGAGUCUUGCUCCAUCGCCCAGGCUGGAGUGCAGUGGCCUGCUGUUGGCUCACUGCAACCUCCGCCUCCCAGGCUCAAGCCAUUCUCCUGUCUCAGCCUCCUGAGUAGCUGGGACUACAGGCGCCUGCCACCACGCCUGGCUAAUUUUUGCAUUUUUGGUAGAGACGGGGUUUCACCUUGUUGAUCAGGCUGAUCUCCAACUCCUGACCUCAGGUCAUCCACCCACCUCCGCCACCGUGCCCGGCCGAAAUUUGUGAUUUUAUAACUAAGAAUUUUUAGUUAAGAACAUUAUCAGUAAAGACAACGUAAUCCCACCCUGGAGAGUUUAUUGGGAGCCCAGGAAUAUUCAUUUUUAAUACACACACACACACACACACACACACACACACACACACACACUGAUCAGAGUAACGGGAGUUUCUCUCAGGAGUCAUACUCCAUGAGCCUGGACCCAGUGGUUCUUUAUGUGGAAACAAAUUUCACCUAUAGGUAACCUGGUAACUGCUAUUUUCUUCUGUGUGCUCUGUCAACAAAGGUAUCAGUGGCUUGCAGGAGAUGCCUUUAAUACUCAGAGCAUUCUAUCUCCCCCUAUCUGGUUUAGAAGGAAGGCCUUCAUUAGUUACCUUUUGAGAAGUUACUAGAACUCUCUAUUAGAGACUUACCCUCCUGACCUGAUAAAAAGGGAUACCCAUGUCUCUAUUAACAGCUUUAUCUCUUUCUACAGUUUUGGGUAUUUGAUAAGGUUAAGGCAAAAUUUUAGUUAUGCUUAAGGAGGAGUUCUUUUUUCACAAUUACAGAGAAAAUUUUGGUUUGUUGAAGAUUGCAGAAACAGCAAUGGUAAUGUAAGACAGUUUUGGCCUUUAAUUUUUUUCUUGAAACUCUACAGUAUACUACAAUAGUGAAGGAAACUAUUAUCAUGAGAGAUCCUUCUGAAUAGGAUGUCUUUCUGAGUUCCACUAUUCAGUUACAAAACUCCUUAAUGCUUAAAAUUCAUUAUGAAAAUUAGAUUUAUUUUAAAUACUUUCAAGUGUAUACAUUUUUAUUUCAUAAUUUUUAUUGUCUUUUAACUAAAGCAUUUAGUUCAUUUAUAUUUACUGUGUACCUUUUAUAUUUAAUAAAUAUAUUUACUUAUUAAAAGAUUA